GCAGGACGCCAUACUGGACGCCAAGUGGGAGGAACUUCAAGGCUGUCCCCUGCGGGCCUCCCGCUCUGCUUCUGCGAAGGUCUGGUCCUGGCUCCCUCUGCCAUCCUGCCCAGCUCCAAGGCUAAAAUAGGUUCUAGUUCUGUAUGGGUAGGGCCCAUUUCUUUUCUUGCCCUCCUUCCCGGGUCCCUGACACCUCAGCCAUUUUCAGUUCAAAGAGCCUCAUGCCCCCUUUCCAUUUCUGUGCCUUUUAGUUUCAGUGUGGGCAUCUCAUCUUUCCCUUUUCUCCUGGCGACCCUUUAUGCCUCCCUUGGGGUUUCCUGUACUUUCCUCUGUGCCUCUCAGUUUUCUCUGGGGUCCCUGAUACCCAUCUUACCUUAGUAACUCCCAGACUGACCAGGACUAUCCUAGUUUGAGCCUAGUUCCUAGCCUCUGUCCUUUCUUUCAUCCCUCCUCACCAGGUCGCCUUCUCUGACAGUCUGGCCCCCCAACCCCCAAAGUAUCGGGGUUGGAUUGGGUUACAGCUAGCUCUGCCUGGGCCUCCCAGGCCCUUCUCUCCACUUUCCCUUUGUGCCGUUGCCUGGAGACCAAUGGGUUGUGGGGGGCUGAGCCAGAGAGGGAGCUGGGGUGAGGGAUGGCUGGGGCUGUGUGUGUGCGUGUGCGUGUGUGUGUGUGUGUGUGUGUGUGAGAGAGAGAGAGAGAGAUGUCCCCUGCAGCUGGACUAUAAGCCUGGCCCUCAGGUUUCAUUGAAAACAGAUCCUGCAAAAGUUCCAGGUGCCCACACUGGAAACUUGGAGAUCCUGCUUCCCAGACCACAGCUGUGGGGAACUUGGGGUGGAGCAGAGAAGUUUCUGUAUUCAGCUGCCCAGGCAGAGGAGAAUGGGGUCUCCACAGCCUGAAGAAUGAAGACACGACAGAAUAAAGACUCGAUGUCAAUGAGGAGUGGACGGAAGAAAGAGGCCCCUGGGCCCCGGGAAGAACUGAGAUCGAGGGGCCGGGCCUCCCCUGGAGGGGUCAGCACGUCCAGCAGUGAUGGCAAAGCUGAGAAGUCCAGGCAGACAGCCAAGAAGGCCCGAGUAGAGGAAGCCUCCACCCCAAAGGUCAACAAGCAGGGUCGGAGUGAGGAGAUCUCAGAGAGUGAAAGUGAGGAGACCAAUGCACCAAAAAAGACCAAAACUGAGCAGGAACUCCCUCGGCCACAGUCUCCCUCCGAUCUGGAUAGCUUGGACGGGCGGAGCCUUAAUGAUGAUGGCAGCAGCGACCCUAGGGAUAUCGACCAGGACAACCGAAGCACGUCCCCCAGUAUCUACAGCCCUGGAAGUGUGGAGAAUGACUCUGACUCAUCUUCUGGCCUGUCCCAGGGCCCAGCCCGCCCCUACCACCCACCUCCACUCUUUCCUCCUUCCCCUCAACCGCCAGACAGCACCCCUCGACAGCCAGAGGCUAGCUUUGAACCCCAUCCUUCUGUGACACCCACUGGAUAUCAUGCUCCCAUGGAGCCCCCCACAUCUCGAAUGUUCCAGGCUCCUCCUGGGGCCCCUCCCCCUCACCCACAGCUCUAUCCUGGGGGCACUGGUGGAGUUUUGUCUGGACCCCCAAUGGGUCCCAAGGGGGGAGGGGCUGCCUCAUCAGUGGGGGGCCCUAAUGGGGGUAAGCAGCACCCCCCACCCACUACUCCCAUUUCAGUAUCAAGCUCUGGGGCUAGUGGUGCUCCCCCAACAAAGCCGCCUACCACUCCAGUGGGUGGUGGGAACCUACCUUCUGCUCCACCACCAGCCAACUUCCCCCAUGUGACACCGAACCUGCCUCCCCCACCUGCCCUGAGACCCCUCAACAAUGCAUCAGCCUCUCCCCCUGGCCUGGGGGCCCAACCACUACCUGGUCAUCUGCCCUCUCCCCACGCCAUGGGACAGGGUAUGGGUGGACUUCCUCCUGGCCCAGAGAAGGGCCCAACUCUGGCUCCUUCACCCCACUCUCUGCCUCCUGCUUCCUCUUCUGCUCCAGCGCCCCCCAUGAGGUUUCCUUAUUCAUCCUCUAGUAGUAGCUCUGCAGCAGCCUCCUCUUCCAGUUCUUCCUCCUCUUCCUCUGCCUCCCCCUUCCCAGCUUCCCAGGCAUUGCCCAGCUACCCCCACUCUUUCCCUCCCCCAACAAGCCUCUCUGUCUCCAAUCAGCCCCCCAAGUAUACUCAGCCUUCUCUCCCAUCCCAGGCUGUGUGGAGCCAGGGUCCCCCACCACCUCCUCCCUAUGGCCGCCUCUUAGCCAACAGCAAUGCCCAUCCAGGCCCCUUCCCUCCCUCUACUGGGGCCCAGUCCACCGCCCACCCACCAGUCUCAACACAUCACCAUCACCACCAGCAACAGCAACAGCAGCAGCAGCAGCAGCAGCAGCAGCAGCAGCAGCAGCAGCAGCAUCACGGAAACUCUGGGCCCCCUCCUCCUGGAGCAUUUCCCCACCCACUGGAGGGCGGUAGCUCCCACCACGCACACCCUUACGCCAUGUCUCCCUCCCUGGGGUCUCUGAGGCCCUACCCACCAGGGCCAGCACACCUGCCCCCACCUCACAGCCAGGUGUCCUACAGCCAAGCAGGCCCCAAUGGCCCUCCAGUCUCUUCCUCUUCCAACUCUUCCUCUUCCACUUCUCAAGGGUCCUACCCAUGUUCACACCCCUCCCCUUCCCAGGGCCCUCAAGGGGCGCCCUACCCUUUCCCACCGGUGCCUACGGUCACCACCUCUUCGGCUACCCUUUCCACGGUCAUUGCCACCGUGGCUUCCUCGCCAGCAGGCUACAAAACGGCCUCCCCACCUGGGCCCCCACCGUACGGAAAGAGAGCCCCGUCCCCGGGGGCCUACAAGACAGCCACCCCACCCGGAUACAAACCCGGGUCGCCUCCCUCCUUCCGAACGGGGACCCCACCGGGCUAUCGAGGAACCUCGCCACCUGCAGGCCCAGGGACCUUCAAGCCGGGCUCGCCCACCGUGGGACCUGGGCCCCUGCCACCUGCGGGGCCCUCAGGCCUGCCAUCGCUGCCACCACCACCUGCGGCCCCUGCCUCAGGGCCGCCCCUGAGCGCCACGCAGAUCAAACAGGAGCCGGCUGAGGAGUAUGAGACCCCCGAGAGCCCGGUGCCCCCAGCCCGCAGCCCCUCGCCCCCUCCCAAGGUGGUAGAUGUACCCAGCCAUGCCAGUCAGUCUGCCAGGUUCAACAAACACCUGGAUCGCGGCUUCAACUCGUGCGCGCGCAGCGACCUGUACUUCGUGCCACUGGAGGGCUCCAAGCUGGCCAAGAAGCGGGCCGACCUGGUGGAGAAGGUGCGGCGCGAGGCCGAGCAGCGCGCGCGCGAAGAAAAGGAGCGCGAGCGCGAGCGGGAACGCGAGAAAGAGCGCGAGCGCGAGAAGGAGCGCGAGCUUGAACGCAGCGUGAAGUUGGCUCAGGAGGGCCGUGCUCCGGUGGAAUGCCCAUCUCUGGGCCCAGUGCCCCAUCGCCCUCCAUUUGAACCGGGCAGUGCGGUGGCUACAGUGCCCCCCUACCUGGGUCCUGACACUCCAGCCUUGCGCACUCUCAGUGAAUAUGCCCGGCCUCAUGUCAUGUCUCCUGGCAAUCGCAACCAUCCAUUCUACGUGCCCCUGGGGGCAGUGGACCCGGGGCUCCUGGGUUACAAUGUCCCGGCCCUGUACAGCAGUGAUCCAGCUGCCCGGGAGAGGGAACGGGAAGCCCGUGAACGAGACCUCCGUGACCGCCUCAAGCCUGGCUUUGAGGUGAAGCCUAGUGAGCUGGAACCCCUACAUGGGGUCCCUGGGCCGGGCUUGGAUCCCUUUCCCCGACAUGGGGGCCUGGCUCUGCAGCCUGGCCCACCUGGCCUGCACCCUUUCCCCUUUCAUCCGAGCCUGGGGCCCCUGGAGCGAGAACGUCUAGCGCUGGCAGCUGGGCCAGCCCUGCGGCCUGACAUGUCCUAUGCUGAGCGGCUGGCAGCUGAGAGGCAGCACGCAGAAAGGGUGGCGGCCCUGGGCAAUGACCCACUGGCCCGGCUGCAGAUGCUCAAUGUGACUCCCCAUCACCACCAGCACUCCCACAUCCACUCGCACCUGCACCUGCACCAGCAAGAUGCUAUCCAUGCAGCCUCUGCCUCGGUGCACCCUCUCAUUGACCCCCUGGCCUCAGGGUCUCACCUUACCCGGAUCCCCUACCCAGCUGGAACUCUCCCUAACCCCCUGCUUCCUCACCCUCUGCACGAGAACGAAGUUCUUCGUCACCAGCUCUUUGCUGCCCCUUACCGGGACCUGCCGGCCUCCCUUUCUGCCCCGAUGUCAGCAGCUCAUCAGCUGCAGGCCAUGCACGCACAGUCAGCUGAGCUGCAGCGCUUGGCGCUGGAACAGCAGCAGUGGCUGCAUGCCCAUCACCCGCUGCACAGUGUGCCGCUGCCUGCCCAGGAGGACUACUACAGUCACCUGAAGAAGGAAAGCGACAAGCCACUGUAGAACCUGCGAUCAAGAGAGCACCAUGGCUCCUACAUUGGACCUUGGAGCACCCCCACCCUCCCCCCACCGUGCCCUUGGCCUGCCACCCAGAGCCAAGAGGGUGCUGCUCAGUUGCAGGGCCUCCGCAGCUGGACAGAGAGUGGGGGAGGGAGGGACAGACAGAAGGCCAAGGCCCGAUGUGGUGUGCAGAGGUGGGGAGGUGGCGAGGAUGGGGACAGAAAGCGCACAGAAUCUUGGACCAGGUCUCUCUUCCUUGUCCCCCCUGCUUUUCUCCUCCCCCAUGCCCAACCCCUGUGGCCGCCGCCCCUCCCCUGCCCCGUUGGUGUGAUUAUUUCAUCUGUUAGAUGUGGCUGUUUUGCGUAGCAUCGUGUGCCACCCCUGCCCCUCCCCGAUCCCUGUGUGCGCGCCCCCUCUGCAAUGUAUGCCCCUUGCCCCUUCCCCACACUAAUAAUUUAUAUAUAUAAAUAUCUAUAUGACGCUCUUAAAAAAACAUCCCAACCAAAACCAACCAAACAAAAACAUCCUCACAACUCCCCAGGAA